AGAAGAAAACAGUUCCACGUUGCUUGAAAUUGAAAAUCAAGAUAAAAAUGUUCACAAUUAAGCUCCUUCUUUUUAUUGUUCCUCUAGUUAUUUCCUCCAGAAUUGAUCAAGACAAUUCAUCAUUUGAUUCUCUAUCUCCAGAGCCAAAAUCAAGAUUUGCUAUGUUAGACGAUGUAAAAAUUUUAGCCAAUGGCCUCCUUCAGUUGGGACAUGGUCUUAAAGACUUUGUCCAUAAGACGAAGGGCCAAAUUAAUGACAUAUUUCAAAAACUCAACAUAUUUGAUCAGUCUUUUUAUGAUCUAUCGCUGCAAACCAGUGAAAUCAAAGAAGAAGAAAAGGAACUGAGAAGAACUACAUAUAAACUACAAGUCAAAAAUGAAGAGGUAAAGAAUAUGUCACUUGAACUCAACUCAAAACUUGAAAGCCUCCUAGAAGAAAAAAUUCUACUUCAACAAAAAGUGAAAUAUUUAGAAGAGCAACUAACUAACUUAAUUCAAAAUCAACCUGAAACUCCAGAACACCCAGAAGUAACUUCACUUAAAACUUUUGUAGAAAAACAAGAUAAUAGCAUCAAAGACCUUCUCCAGACCGUGGAAGACCAAUAUAAACAAUUAAACCAACAGCAUAGUCAAAUAAAAGAAAUAGAAAAUCAGCUCAGAAGGACUAGUAUUCAAGAACCCACAGAAAUUUCUCUAUCUUCCAAGCCAAGAGCACCAAGAACUACUCCCUUUCUUCAGUUGAAUGAAAUAAGAAAUGUAAAACAUGAUGGCAUUCCUGCUGAAUGUACCACCAUUUAUAACAGAGGUGAACAUACAAGUGGCAUGUAUGCCAUCAGACCCAGCAACUCUCAAGUUUUUCAUGUCUACUGUGAUGUUAUAUCAGGUAGUCCAUGGACAUUAAUUCAACAUCGAAUAGAUGGAUCACAAAACUUCAAUGAAACGUGGGAGAACUACAAAUAUGGUUUUGGGAGGCUUGAUGGAGAAUUUUGGUUGGGCCUAGAGAAGAUAUACUCCAUAGUGAAGCAAUCUAAUUAUGUUUUACGAAUUGAGUUGGAAGACUGGAAAGACAACAAACAUUAUAUUGAAUAUUCUUUUUACUUGGGAAAUCACGAAACCAACUAUACGCUACAUCUAGUUGCGAUUACUGGCAAUGUCCCCAAUGCAAUCCCGGAAAACAAAGAUUUGGUGUUUUCUACUUGGGAUCACAAAGCAAAAGGACACUUCAACUGUCCAGAGGGUUAUUCAGGAGGCUGGUGGUGGCAUGAUGAGUGUGGAGAAAACAACCUAAAUGGUAAAUAUAACAAACCAAGAGCAAAAUCUAAGCCAGAGAGGAGAAGAGGAUUAUCUUGGAAGUCUCAAAAUGGAAGGUUAUACUCUAUAAAAUCAACCAAAAUGUUGAUCCAUCCAACAGAUUCAGAAAGCUUUGAAUGAACUGAGGCAAAUUUAAAAGGCAAUAAUUUAAACAUUAACCUCAUUCCAAGUUAAUGUGGUCUAAUAAUCUGGUAUUAAAUCCUUAAGAGAAAGCUUGAGAAAUAGAUUUUUUUUAUCUUAAAGUCACUGUCUAUUUAAGAUUAAACAUACAAUCACAUAACCUUAAAGAAUACCGUUUACAUUUCUCAAUCAAAAUUCUUAUAAUACUAUUUGUUUUAAAUUUUGUGAUGUGGGAAUCAAUUUUAGAUGGUCACAAUCUAGAUUAUAAUCAAUAGGUGAACUUAUUAAAUAACUUUUCUAAAUAAAAAAUUUAGAGACUUUUAUUUUAAAAGGCAUCAUAUGAGCUAAUAUCACAACUUUCCCAGUUUAAAAAACUAGUACUCUUGUUAAAACUCUAAACUUGACUAAAUACAGAGGACUGGUAAUUGUACAGUUCUUAAAUGUUGUAGUAUUAAUUUCAAAACUAAAAAUCGUCAGCACAGAGUAUGUGUAAAAAUCUGUAAUACAAAUUUUUAAACUGAUGCUUCAUUUUGCUACAAAAUAAUUUGGAGUAAAUGUUUGAUAUGAUUUAUUUAUGAAACCUAAUGAAGCAGAAUUAAAUACUGUAUUAAAAUAAGUUCGCUGUCUUUAAACAAAUGGAGAUGACUACUAAGUCACAUUGACUUUAACAUGAGGUAUCACUAUACCUUAUUUGUUAAAAUAUAUACUGUAUACAUUUUAUAUAUUUUAACACUUAAUACUAUGAAAACAAAUAAUUGUAAAGGAAUCUUGUCAGAUUACAGUAAGAAUGAACAUAUUUGUGGCAUCGAGUUAAAGUUUAUAUUUCCCCUAAAUAUGCUGUGAUUCUAAUACAUUCGUGUAGGUUUUCAAGUAGAAAUAAACCUCGUAACAAGUUACUGAACGUUUAAACAGCCUGACAAGCAUGUAUAUAUGUUUAAAAUUCAAUAAACAAAGACCCAGUCCCUAAAUUAUAGAAAUUUAAAUUAUUCUUGCAUGUUUAUCGACAUCACAACAGAUCCCUAAAUCCCUAAAUCCCUAAAGAUUAGAUACAAAUUUUUUACCACAGUAUCACUUGUCAGAAUUUAUUUUUAAAUAUGAUUUUUUAAAACUGCCAGUAAGAAAUUUUAAAUUAAACCCAUUUGUUAAAGGAUAUAGUGCCCAAGUUAUAUGGUGACCUACCUUUGUCAAUACUUAGCAUUAUGUAUUUCAAAUUAUCCAAUAUACAUGUCAUAUAUAUUUUUAUAUGUCACAUAUAUAAAAGAUAUGUAUGAUCUAUGUGAAUCCUAAGUAAAUAUUUUGUUCCAGAAAAGUACAAAAUAAUAAAGGUAAAAAUAAUCUAUAAUUUUCAGGACCACAGACUAAGCUGUCGAAAUUAACGCUGAUUUUUUUAGGGCCAGAAUACCAAAAUGGCUCCUCUCUUCCCCCAAAAUUGGACAAUUUCAAAUGCAAAAUAAUUCAUUAUUUAAUAUAUGAGUUGCUUCCUCUAUUUGGUUUCC